CUGUUUGUCUUUGGGGCUGGAGCUGCAGGGUCAGCCUGGAGCCGCUGCCACAGGGCAUCCUGCAAACUUGCCCCACUCACAUCCACGCUUACCAGUGGGAGCUCUCACUGCACAGCCAGAUGCUGGCUGGGCAAGCACUCGCGUUCUUGGGCCUGACCUGGGGCACUUUCCAGAGCCUGGCCAUCCCCCGGAUUACAGAAUGUGGCCUCUCCUGUUCUCAGGGCUUUGCCUGCAGGAGCCACAGGAACCGGAACAUUUUUAACAGCUUCUGCCGGCCACGCCCCGUGUCCAUGUCCAGGUCAGUCCUGGAGGCCCUGACGUCCUCCACUGCCAUGCAGUGUGUCCCCUCUGACGGCUGCGCGAUGCUCCUGCGUGUACGCGCCUCCAUCACCCUGCAUGAGCGCCUGCGGGGCCUGGAGGCCUGUGCCAUGAGCCUGGACACCCAGGAGACGCAGUGUCAGAGCGUGUGGGUGGCCAGGGCCUCCCACCGGCAGCAGGGGGGGCAGCAGCUCCAAGUGCACUUUGGCUGCUUUGCGGUGAGCGUGGCCCAGCACCUCUAUGUCACCCUGAGGACCAUCCCUCAUUUCUGCGGGGUCCAGCUGGACCAGAGGCACCUCGUGGAAGACUGCGGAGAGGAGGACGUGGGGAGGAGCGUGCCCGACUGCCUCGCGGGGAAGCUCAGCUACUGGGUGGACCGGAGGCGCAAGGCGAUUCUGGUGCAAGUGCCCAGGGCCUCCGGGAGCCCCGACUACUACCUGCGGCUCUGCCUCAAGCGGUUCACCUGCGAGGACGCCGGCGCCCCUGUGCGAGUGACCGCCAACAGCGUCUCCCAGGCCGUCUUCCUGCCCUACAGCCAGGAGCUGCCGUGCCUGUGCCUGGAGGGCUGGUCUGCGACCCCUGACGCGGUGCGGAUCCAGAUCUGCCCCUUUGAAAACGACACUGAGGCACUGGAGGUGCUGUGGGACACGGUCUACUACCACCCGGAGAGCCAGACACUGAGCUGGGAGCCCGCCUGCCCUGUGAGUGGCCAUGUGAGCCUGUGCUGGCGCCCGGGGCCGGGGGCCGGCUGCCGUAAGCUGCAGCAAUCCAGCCAGCUGGUGCAUCGCAGAGUGCAGUACCCGCUGGUGGACACCCAGCCCCAGCUCUGCCUGAAGUUCUCUACCAGUUGGGGGUCCUGGGUGCGGUGCCCUUUCGAACAGCGUCGCUUCCCAACCUGGAAAAUGACCAUCCAGCCUUCGCCCACAAAGGGCCACCUCCGGGUCACCUUCUUCUCGUCCAGCCCCGCCCACUUCCAGGUGCACCUGUGUCACAGGAGGAAGUCACAGCUCCCUGCCUGCCAACGCACACUCCAGGCCAGCCCGCUCCCUUCAGCCUCAGGUGACCUGGCAGCCGCCCCUGCUUUUGCCUUCCUAGACCUUCCCAGGGAGGAGGCCUGUGCCCCAGGCAUCUGCAUCCAGGGCUGGAGGACCGAUGUACACUUCUCCGUCCCCCAGCAGCUCUGCAACCUCCGCUCCAGUGGGUGCCCAUCUCUCAGGGGCCGCAGGAGGCCGAGGACUAGACCUAGGCCUCCCACGGCAGGCUGGGCGUGGCGUGCACUGAACAGGAGACUGGGUGGGGGAAACGGGGAGACCAUCCGGCCCUGAGUCAGGUCAGGCUUCUGCGCCAAACCCAGGUCUGUGCCCAGCACUGCCCUCCAGCCUUGCAUUUCCCUCCACCACACACCGCUGGGCCUCCCGCACGCCCACCCUGGUCUCACUGUCACUGGCCUUGCCUCCUCCUCCCUGGGGGUCCACCUUCCCUGAUCAGAGCUCUGGUUCCAACCGCCAGUGACUUGGGAUGUCCCUUUGCCCACCAGCCACUGAGGCCCAGGCUCCCAGGACCCAGGGUACAUCAGGACAGGACUCUGCCCAGUGGACAGAACUAAGCACAUGUGGCCUGGGUGUGGUCAGGAGCGUGGCUCUGCCUUGGAGUCCAGGAAGGGUCAGAGCUGGCACUCCUACCUGCACCCCUCCCUGUGAGCAAAAGAGCUUGCCUAGCUUCGGGUGGGGUGAACCGCAACAGCCACAGAGGUGGGAGGGGUGGGAGGGGGUGGAUAGGACAGCCUGGCACCCAGGGCCUCUGGAGACCCUUUCCAGGGAGCACCAGUGGGCCAGGCAGGGGUCUCUGGAAUGUCUCCUCAGCUCAGCUGAGCCACAGCCAUUUCAGGGCAGCCUGCUGCCCACAGGACAUGCCCAGGGCCGUGGCAGUACCCGCAGACCUUCAGCUCCCCCUUCUCCCAGCAAGACUUUUUGGCCAAGCCUAGGUCCCCCUCCCUAGCAAAGGUCACCUCCAGCAGAUCACAGACUAAAGGGGCAAUGGCCACCUGCUGGUCAGGUGUCCCUGGGGCUGGCACCUGCCACUGUGGAGUGCCCAUGCUAUGCUGGGCAAGUCCACGGCCCCAGGGACAGGCCUGGAGGCAGCAGGAGGACCGGGCCUGGCUCAGGUGGGGGGAUCUGGGGGUCAUACACACUCCUCUUGGGGCCAGGGUGGGCUCCUCCUUCACUUGUCUGCUGAGCCUCCCUGCAGAUGGAAGGCUGCUGUCCACAGCCACUGGCACCCCAGGACUGGGCAGCCCCCUCCCCUUCCCUCACAUGUCUCAGCCUCGCACAGUGGGGGCAGGGCUGGGAGGUGGUGUCCCAGCCAGUACCACCCCUACGUCUCUCUCCAGCUGCACCCACCCACAUGGGACGGCAGCCUGAGGCCAGGAAUCUCCUCACGAACAAGUAGGUGCCAGGGACACAUUGCUGGGGGGCAGGAGGCCAAGGCACAGCCUCGGACAGCUGAGCCAGGCCCCCCUCCGAGAGUGUGGGGUGUUCUCACCUGACUGUGGGGCCUAGGCACCUGCUGGCUGUCCUGGGGCUACAGCUCCAUGGGGCCCUCAGGGGCUCUGGGUCACAUAAAAGACCUUCAGCCCUGUCCUGAGUCCCCUGGGAACAGCAGGAGCUGGGUGGGCUACCCCUUCCCCGGAUGGCCCAGGUGCUGGACCCCAGCCUCCCUCUCAGACAAUUCAUGGUCAUGGCCACUGUCCCUGGCCCUGAAGACAAGGCCCUGGCAGCUGCCUGGAGCUUCCCCAGUGCUCUGGGGUGCAGGGUGCAACCCCACCCUUCCUGUAGCUGAUCAGGCCCGAGGUGGUCAAGGAUCACCCCAGUUUCUGCCCAGGGCACCCCACACUGGCUGGAGUCCACCUCUCCUGUCUGUGCAUCCUUGGGUGCUGAGCUUCACUGGGGCACCCGCCCCACUCGGACCCCUCCAGAGGGUCUCAGCUUCCCCAGAUCCCAGCCCCACUCACCCAGCAACGGUCAGUCACUUCCUGUGGUCUCAGAGGCCACCUGCCUGGGGGCCACCUGCUGGGAUGUGCGGUUCUCAGACAUUCCAAGUGGCACAUCCAGGUCCCAGCCAGGGGUGCCCAGCAGUGGCCUGUGCAGUGGGCCAUGGGGUCGGCCCUUGAAGACUUCUCGUGUGGGUCACGUAGGCUCUCCGGCUUCCCCGCUGAGCCACCCUCUGGAGCCUGGACAUCGUCUCACCUGAGUGCUGUGCAGGACCACAUGCCCAGCCUGUCCCAGCGGUGGUCGCACCCCAUCUGCAGAUGCACUCCCACCGCAGUCUGGGCCCAGGCUGCCCUCUUCCAGCUGGCCGUGGGCCGCUGGGCCUUCUUUUCCCUCCUGCAACAGAGGCUGCUAUGUCCCAUAGACUGGAGAGGGGGCUGCAGAGCGAGUAAGUCCCCGCCACUCAGUAAACAUUGGUCCAGGGGUAGCUGUUAAAAUGGAGCUUGGGCCUGGCUGGAUGGUGACGGCACCAGGGACAAGUCUGGAGUGCGGGUGUCGUGGAGCCAUCCCCACCAGGCUGGACCCAAGAGCACCCCAAAGGCGUGGGAGGCCGCACCCCCAUGGGCAUGUGGGGGGCAGGGAGCACCUUGGGACUCAGGGGAGGUGCCGGGUCUCUGGGAGUGGAUUUGAGGUCAGCGUCACAUGGUGUGACCAGACAUCCCCAUCCAAGUGUCCCCAUAAAGGACCAGUGGUGGAGACACCCUGGGGAUGCGGAGGUCAGGCCAGGUGAGGGGCUUUAGAAGCUGGGUUUGAGCACCAGGGGCAGGGAGGCCAGUGGGGGGCAUGGACAGGGUGUCCCUCCCUAACCUGGAGAUCAGGGGCAUGGGGGGAUGCAGGCUGCCACUCGCCCAGGUGCCCUUCCCUAACCUGGAGAUCAGGGGAAUGGGGGGAUACAGGCUGCCACUCACCCAGGUGCCCCUCCCUAGCCUGGGGGAGGUCAGGGGCACAGUGGGGGUGGGGGGCACAGCACAAGCUGCCACUCUGCUCUCUCCAUGUCUCCUCUGGAGACCCCGUCCGCCCCCAGCCAGAAAACAAGUGUCCCGGCUCAGCAGGGCAGUCCCCGCCCCAGGUUCCUGCUCCUGCCUCCUGGACCAGCCAGGGGUGCUCCCUGUGGUGCACAAAGACCCCUGCUCUGACCCAGGGCUACUCCGGGAAUCCUGGCCACCGUGGAGGUGGGGCUGGGGAGGAUUGGCCAGACCAGGGUCACAGAGCUGAGCUCCUGCCUGACGGGUGUGGGCUCCCUCAAGCCUUCCACAGAUGGGGGAAACUGAGUCUUUUCUUCUGCAGAUGGGGGAAACUGAGUCUUUGGGGACUGUUAAGAGGCUGUGUUCAGAUCUCAGCUGUCCUACUGUCCCUCCCAGACAAGGGAGGAACCUGCUGGAGGACACACGCGUGCUGCCACCAGGCGGCAGUGGCUCUUAGUGCUGGUGCUGAGCCGGAUCAGCCGCCCCAGCACCCAACACGGAGCGCCCACAGCCCAGUGCACCCACCGCCUCCUUGGCCAGGGACGCUGCCCUCCCUCCACCACCACCGCCGGAAACCCACCCCCACACCUGCCAGGAGAAAAGUGCUGAGGACCCCGGGCCCCAGAAAGGGGGGUGCGGUAGGGGCGGGCAGGAGCACCUGUACUGGGGUGCACAGCCCUGCUCACAUCUGGGCCACAGUAUAACACGGGUGAGCCUUGGACGCCCGCCUGCCUCAUUCACUCAUGACACACAGCUGAGCAGGCCUUGGGCCCUGGGCCCCGACCCAGCACCGGGAACAAACAACACUGGCAAAGAUCCCGGGCCCUGCAGCUGGGGGACCAAGUCUGGGGCUGCCUGGCACUAAGGAGGGUCUUGGGUCAGAGUGUCAGUGCUGACACCAGGACAGUCCCAGGCAAACUGGGAUCAUGGAGCUGACCUUUGCAUGAGAGAGACAACCAGAGCCAAGUGACAUAAGUAAGCGAGGGGGCGUGGCUGGUGCCAGUGUGGGGUGAGGAAUGAGGCUGGGAGCACGAUGGGGAGUGUGGGGAGCUGCAAUCUGAAAUAGGGUGGGUCUGGGCACGGUGGCUCCCGCCUGUAAUCCCAGCACUUUGGGAGACCAAGGCGGGUGGAUUACUUAAGGUCAGGAGUUUGAGACCACCUGGCCAACAUGGGGAAACCCCAGCUCUACUAAAAAUACAAAAAUUAACCAGGCAUUGUGGUGGGCACCUGUAAUCCCAGCUACUCAGGAGGCUGAGGCAGGAGAAUCGCUUGAACCCAGAAGGCAGAGGUUGCAGUGAGCUGAGAUCAUGCCACUGCACUCCAUCCUGGGUGACUGAAUGAGACACCAUCUUAAAAAUAAUAAACUAAAAAUUAAAAUGAAAUAAAAUAGGGUGGGGCCAGGCAUGGUGUUGCACACCUGUAAUCCCAGCACUUUGGGAGGCCAAGGCAGGAGGAUUGUUUGAGCCUGGGGGAUUGAGGCUGCAGUGAGCCAUGAUUGCACCACUGCACUCCAGCCUGGGUAACAGAGCAAGACCCUAUUUCAAUAGAUAUAAAAUUUCAAAAAUAGGGUGGUCCCUGGGAGGCUCAGACAAGGUGAUGUGUGAACAGAGACUGCAGAGGCAGGGCCUUUGCAUUGCCCGGCUCUAACAGGGUCCCUGACUGCCUCACGGAAGAGCAGCGAGAGUCAGCUUGUGGAGGGCAGGCAGGUGGGGAGAAGUGCAGAAGGUGAGGCCUUCGGGGUGUCCUGGCACGCAAGUGUGAAUAAAAGUGACCAACGUUUUGGCCUCAGCUCCUUGUGGACAAAUUUGUGUCCACAAAUUUGUGGAAAAAUUCUUUGUGGACAAAGGAUAGACAGAACUCAAAGUCAUCCGUCUGCUCACUGAGAUAAAUGCAUAUCUGAUUUCUUCCUUUGGAAAGGCUAAUCAGAAACUCAAAAGAAUGCAACUGUUUGUCUCUUAUCUGUGACCCAGAAGCCCCCUCUCCAAUUUGAAUUGUCCCACUUUUCCAGACAGAACCAAUGUACUUCUUACAUAUAUUGACUGAUGUCUCAUUUCUCCUUAUAAUGUAUAAAACCAAGCUGUGCCCGGACCACCUCAGGCACAUGUCAGGACCUCCUGAGGCUGUGUCAUGGGCUCGUGUCCUCAACCUUGGCCAAAUAAACUUCCUGAAUUGACGGA